GUUCUGAACUUCUAUGUCCUUACAACAAGGUAAUCUAGAAAAUUCUUCCAAGAGAGAAUGACUGUUUCCCCUUGAGAAACAAUUUUAUUUCCAAACCCCUUUCUAGAUUGUUUUCAUGAUUCAGGUGUGUAGUUGAAGCAGAAUGUCUCCUCUACAUACUACAUGCUUGAUUUUGAGAAUACUUUCUUAAUAUCUUUUGGCUUCGGUUUUCUAAUUAUAAAAUAGUUGAAAAUGCUUUAUGAUUUUAUAAGUAUAUAAAAAGCAUUAGGUUCAAAACAGAGGCUAUAAGUGUGUUUAGCCAACUAUUAGACACAAUGAAACUUCCCGUGAUUAAUUAGCUACAACUACACUAAGCAGUUCAUCAAAAUGUAGGGAUUAGAAAUGAUGCUGAAAGGGCAAGAAUAGGCCGGGGUGGCCUCUACCUGGGUCUAACUUGCUGUCUGACUCUCUCUCAGCUCCUGAACACCCGCACCAAGAUGUCCUGCCAGCAGAACCAGCAGCAGUGCCAGCCCCCUCCCAAGUGCAUCCCCAAGUGCCCUCCCAAGUGCCUCACCCCUAGAUGCCCCCCAAAGUGUCCCCCUAAGUGUCCUCCAGUCUCUUCCUGCUGCAGUGUCAGCUCCGGAGGCUGCUGUGGCUCCAGCUCUGGGGGAAGCUGUGGCUCCAGCUCUGGGGGUUGCUGCAGUUCUGGGGGAGGUGGCUGCUGCCUGAGCCACCACAGGCGCCGUAGGUCCCACUGCCACAGACCCCAGAGCUCUGGCUGCUGCAGCCAGCCCUCCGGGGGCUCCAGCUGCUGUGGAGGAGGGAGUGGCCAGCACUCUGGAGGCUGCUGCUAAAGUGGAUCCUGAGCCUAGAAGAACACAAAUGGCCAAAUAUUUCCCUUCCGUCUUCCUUCUCCUUCUGGGCCUGCCCAUGUUGUUGAGAGGUCUUGGUGAGGGCUCAACUCAAGCAUAGAGGAUUCUUCUGUCUUGGAGUUCAGAGGCCCAAAACUUCUCCCCCAAAGCCAAGCCAUUUAAUGACCUCAGUUUGCGUAUGUGUGGUUGCUCUGGGAAGCCCAAAGCACAGACCUAUAUCCCUUUGCAGCUUGUCUUUUUGCAUAGCUCAGCCUGAUGUGAAACAAUAAAACCAGAAAUAUGCAUUC